GAGGCCAAACUUCCUGCUGAAGCUCUGUGGCCUCUUUUGGGGUGGGGGCGGGGGUCCAGGCAGAAAGAAACUGUCUGCUGCUCAAGACCCACAGGACGCCGGGAAGACUAAAUGAUCACUGCCCCCAGUGAAUAUGGUGAAGAAGCUGGUGAUGGCCCAGAAGCGGGGAGAGACACGAGCCCUUUGCCUGGGUGUAACCAUGGUGGUGUGUGCCGUCAUCACCUACUACAUCCUGGUCACGACUGUGCUGCCCCUCUACCAGAAAAGCGUGUGGACCCAGGAAUCCAAGUGCCACCUGAUUGAGACCAACAUCAGGGACCAGGAGGAGCUGAAGGGCAAGAAGGUGCCCCAGUACCCAUGCCUGUGGGUCAACGUGUCAGCUGCCGGCAGGUGGGCUGUGCUGUACCACACGGAGGACACUCGGGACCAGAACCAGCAGUGCUCCUACAUCCCAGGCAGCGUGGACAAUUACCAGACGGCCCGGGCCGACGUGGAGAAGGUCAGAGCCAAAUUCCAAGAGCAGCAGGUCUUCUACUGCUUCUCCGCACCUCGGGGGAACGAAACCAGCGUCCUAUUCCAGCGCCUCUACGGGCCCCAGGCCCUCCUCUUCUCCCUCUUCUGGCCCACCUUCCUGCUGACCGGUGGCCUCCUCAUUAUCGCCAUGGUGAAGAGCAACCAGUACCUGUCCAUCCUGGCGGCCCAGAAGUAGAGCCAUCCAUCCAUGCCAUACCACUUGUCAGGGCACAGGGGACUGGCUGGGCCCCCAGGGCUGCUCCCCACUUGCAGCACAAUGCCUUCUCCACCUGCCCUCCCACUCUUCCAGUCCAAUCCACGCUGUCUUCUGUUGCAGGACUAACCUUUGAGAAAUCCUUUUGUGAAGUCAUUGCCUGCUCAAGAAUGUACAGUGGCUCCCCAAUGCCUUGGAGGCCAUAAGGCCAGCCAGUUCUAGCUCUCUAUUACCUGUCCCCACUCAACUGACUCAUACCUGUUUCCGGCUGCAUCACUAUGUGCCCCACAGAGAACGAUGAUCGUCACCUCUGUGCCUGAGUUCUCCCUGUUGUCUCAAAGCGGUACCCAUCCUCCCCCAGAAGCUGUCCCCAGCGAGCCUCCCUUCUUUGUUUGAAUUCUCUAAUAAGAGCAACAGCAGCUCCCAUUUCUAGAACACAUUUACAGUAUUACUAUUUUCUAGGAUAUAAAGUGCCAUAUAUAUUUUUAAUUCCAAUAUUAAUAAAUGUAUGCCAAACAACAAUCAGCUGCAAGGAAACACAUGAGAACUCAUCAAAAUUUUAGCGGUGGGAUGGUGGUUAAUUUCUGUUUUCUUCCUUAUCCCCUUUUUAUUUUUGCUGCUUUUCUAAAUUUUUGAUUAUAGGAAGGGUGUGUUUCGUUUGCUUUUAAUCAGAAAAGCCAUGGUAGAUGCCAUUUUGGAAAAGUUGAAAGAGUGUGUCCCCCUCACAGAAAAAGAUGGAAGUGGGUCUGGGGACGGAGUUGGGUUCCAGUCAGAGACAGGCCAUUCAGAACACACAAUCUUAAAAACCCCUCUGGGCCGGGCGCGGUGGCUCACUCCUGUAAUCCCAGCACUUUGGGAGGCCGAGGCUGGUGGAUCACGAGGUCAGGAGAUCAAGACCAUCCUGGCUAACAUGGUGAAACCCCGUCUCUACUAAAAAUACAAAAAAUUAGCCAGGCGUGGUGGUGGGCACCUGUGGUCCCAGCUACUCAGGAGGCUGAGGCAGGAGAAUGGCGUGAACCCGGGGUUCGGAGCUUGCAGUGAGCCGAGAUUGUGCCACUGCACUCCAGCCUGGUGAUAGAACAAGACUCCGUCUCAAAAAAAAAACAAAAAACAAAAAAUGAAAAACAACCCUCUGGAGGAAAGGUCAUGAUAUAGAGGAGGAUUUGUUAUUUAAAUUGAGGGUAUGGACUCUGGCACUGAGCCUGCUGGGGAAGCCUAUCUCAGAUUUGAAAAGGGCAAAAUGGGAAGAAGCCAUCACCUUUACCAUUCCCACUCCAGGAAGUUUUCCUAGAACGAUGACUGUCCAAGUGUGGUCCCUGGGCCAGCAGCAUCAGGAUCCUGUGGCAGCUUGUGAGAAAUGCACACUCUCAGGCCCCUGUCCCAGCCCCACCACGCCAGAAGCCCUGCACGGGGUGGGGGUAGCAAUGUUCUGUGUUCUAACAAUGCGUAGGGGAUUCUGUGGCACACCUCGAGCCAGAGAACUACCGGUGUAGGAAGUGAGCGUCCUGUCGCGAGGAUUUUCAGAGCAGGUGAGUGACCAUUCGGCAGGGCCAGUCCUGAGCUGGGUGUGAAGUUAGGCUGGUGUCUGAAGUUUCUUCCAGUGUUGUGAGUCCAAGAUGCAGAUCUUGGGUUUGAAUCCUGUCUCUACUCUGCCCGAUUUCAUCUCUUUGAUUCUUAGUUUUUUCAUCUAUAAAAGAAGGACUCUUUCUGGAUAGUUGGGAGGGCUGAAGGAAUGUUUGACACAUCAUAGGUGUUUAAAAUGGCAACUAUAGUUUUUUUUGUUUGUUUUGUGUGUGUGUUUUUUUCUUAACUUUCAUUUUAAGUUGCAGGGUACACGUUCAGGUUUGUUACAUAGGUACACUUGUGUCAAGGGAGUUUGUUGUGCAGAUUAUUUCAUCACCCAGGUAUUAAGUCUAGUACCCAUUAUUAAAGAAAAUGUGGUACGUAUACGUCAUGGAAUAUUAUGCAGCCAUAAAAAGGAAGGAGAUCAUGUCCUUUGCAGGGACAUGGAUGGAGCUGGAGGCCAAAUAUUAUCCUUAGCAAACUAACACAGGGACACAAAACUAAAUACUGUAUAUUCUCACUUAUAAGUGGGAGCUAAAUGAUGAAAACACAUGGACACAAAGAGGGGAACAACACACACUGAGGCCUAUUGGAGGGCGGGAGGUAGGAGGAGGGAGAGGAUCAGGGAAAAAGAGCUAUUGUUAGUAACAAGAAAAAGUCGGCCGGGCGUGGUGGCUCACACCUGUAAUCCCAGCACUUUGGGAGGCCGAGGUGGGCAGAUCACGAGGUCAGGAGAUCGAGACCAUCCUGGCUAACACGGUGAAACCCUGUCUCUACUAAAAAAUAGAAAAAAUCAUAGCCGGGCGUGGUGGUAGCCGCCUGUAGUCCCAGCUGCUCAGGAGGCUGAGGCAGAAGAAUGGCGUGAACCCGGGAGGCGGAGCUUGCAGUGAGCCGAGAUCGCGCCACGGCACUCCAGCCUGGGUAACAGAGCAAGACUCUGUCUCAAAAAAAAAAAAAAAAAAAAAAAAAAAAGAAUAAGUCAUGAAUACUCAGAAACUUCCAGAAGUUAUACUGACAAUGUUAUCUGGCAUGUAUGGGUGCUUAUUUAUUCUGUGCCAGGCACUGUACUAAUUAGUUUGCCUUGGAAAAAAAAAUGAGAUACUCCUGAACCUGCCUCACAGAUGAUGAGAAGCAACAGAGGACAGUGGCUAAGUAUGUGGACUUGGGAUGUGCACUGUUUGGGUUCAAAUUCCAGCUGUGCUGUUCACAAGCUGGGUGACUUUGGACGAAUAACCUUUCUGUGCCUGUUUCCUCGUUUGCAAAACGAAACUGAUAAUAGUAUCUUUCCAUAGAGUUUUGGCAUGAAACAAAUUUUUAUGUAAAUUUCCUAGGAUAGUGACAUAUGGUAAGUGCUAUCUAAGUUACUAUGAAAAACUGAGGCUGUAAGAGGUAACUGGCCAAGGCCAUCUGUAAAGUGAGGGGCUAGGACUCAAGCCUGGAGCUGUGUGUUCCAGUACCUGGCAUCUCAACCACAGAACUCAGCAGAGCCAGCUGUGAAGGGCUGAGGGACAGAGCCAGCUGUGAAGGGCUGAGGGGCAGAGCCAGCUGUGAAGGGCUGAGGGGCAGAGCCAGCUGUGAAGGGCUGAGGGACACAGCCACUCAAAGCCACAGGGGCCAGGCAGGGAGCUGCGUUGCAUCCCUGGAACCCAGGUGCCCUCAUGCAGGUUGGAGUUCUGAGGGGAGGCCCUGGCAUCUGCACCAGCAUCUGCCAAUUCCAGCCAGGGAGCCCAGAGGUAUCCCUGUGGCCUCCAGUUUCUUACCUGGUGGACCUUCCUUCCAAAGGCAGGCAGCUCAUCAUUCCCUGGAAUUUUUUCCUUCUGGGGUCAGGGAAGUCUCAAAGGUCCUCAUGUGAGUCUUUUAAGAAAGUCUUAAUUGUAAUAUUGUACUAUAGUUUUGCAAAAUAUUAAAUAUUACCAUUGGGGACAUUAGGUAGAGGGGGCACGGAAUGUCUCUGUAUUAUUUCGUAAAGCUUCAUGUGAAUCUACAAUUAUCUCAAAAAUUUAAGUUAAAAAAGGAAGAAAAAUAAGAAAGGAAGUCCCAACUUGGAGUCUGAUUUAAAGGGUCUAUUUUGUCAAUGGUUUCCAUGCACCUGAAUUUGGGACUAAAAUACACAGAAACUCAGAAUACCCAAACAAUCCCUGCAGGGGAAAAGGCCAUGUUCCUCUAGAAAAAUUAGUAUGUGAGGAUGCCUAACCCCCACUGUCCCAUAAAUUAUUAAUGAUGACCUUCAUUUGCUUGAGAUAGAUGUUCUCCUCCUGUCAAUAAAGACUGGCCUUCUAGCAAAUGCCACAACUGUCUGCUGCUCACAGAACUUUAUGCACGGGAUAAGCAUGAAAUAAUGGGAAUUUAGGCAUGAUGGAGUUAGACCCUGUGCCUACGUGUUUUUUUGCAAUAAUAUCUGCCUGGGAGCAGAGAACCUUCAUCAGUUCUUAAUAAACCACUCUGCUAAUGA